AAGUGAAGGUGGAAGCGGCCGCGGCGGCAGCAGGUAGGGGGAGGGGCAGGCGAGGGGCCGUAGGGCCUGGAAGGCGCCAGCCGGGCCGGCGGGCGGUGUGAUUGAUCCGCGUCCCCUGGAGCUGGAGGCUCGGGGGAAAGGGCCAGCACGGAGCGGGCGCUCGGUUGCUGCGCACAAAGGCUGAGGCUCCAAGAGCUGCAGGGCGUGUUUGGGGUGCGCGCGAGGUUGUGUGCAAGGUCCGGGGCGCUUGGCACCGGCCACGCAAGGGUGUCAGUCUCCACGCGGACGGGCUGCGUAGGGACUCGUAGGGACGGGUUCCGGGUGCUGGGCCCGGCCGGUCUCCUCUGUCCUACCCAUCCCUUCCCGAUGGCGCUUGCCUUCGCGGGCCGUCGGGGGAGAACGGGAGAAGAUUGUGGGACCGCUCUCCUCUCCCUUUCUCCACUCGUGGGACCUACACGGAGACUGAGUAGAGGAGAGAAGCGACGGCACCAAUCUUUGUGUUUGUUUUUAAAUUGUGGAGGGAAACAGCCAUGCUCUGCUACCCUCCUCUUACUGGAGAGCUGUCAAAAAUUUUGGGGAUCCCCUAUUCCCCCGCGUUUAGUCCCCCUGCAGAUAGAAAAUUGAGGCCAAAUGUAGUAACUAACUGGGGCAAGGUCACACUGGGAGUGGCAGAGCCGGGAUUCGAAUCCGGAGGUUCUGACAGGGCCACCCUCUUACCUCCACAUCAGCACUUCCUUCUCUCCUCCGCGCAGCCUGAACUGAUGCCCUUGUAGCCUAUAUUGAUUCCGGCUCGAGCCUAGAGAGGACGUGUUCUCUGGACUUAGGGGUAGACAGACACUGGGGAGGGUUAGUGACCCGAGGAGGUUGAUGACCCUGGGAGUCUGGGUCUUGGCUGAGGCUUUCCGUCCCUGAAAGACCCCAGGUCUGUCUCCCAUGUCAUUCACCUCGUUGCUGUGUUUUCUCAGACCCCAGAGUCAGAAGGAGUGAGAACCCUGACCCCUAAUCCCACUGCAUCCAGCCAAUAGGAGCCCAGCCACCAUGGCGGAGCUGCAGGAGGUGCAGAUCACAGAGGAGAAGCCACUGUUGCCAGGACAGACGCCUGAGGCGGCCAAGGAGGCUGAGUUAGCUGCCCGAAUCCUCCUGGACCAGGGACAGACUCACUCUGUGGAGACACCAUACGGCUCUGUCACUUUCACUGUCUAUGGCACCCCCAAACCCAAACGCCCAGCGAUCCUUACCUACCACGAUGUGGGACUCAACUAUAAAUCUUGCUUCCAGCCACUGUUUCAGUUCGAGGACAUGCAGGAAAUCAUUCAGAACUUUGUGCGGGUUCAUGUGGAUGCCCCUGGAAUGGAAGAGGGAGCCCCUGUGUUCCCUUUGGGAUAUCAGUACCCAUCUCUGGACCAGCUUGCAGACAUGAUCCCUUGCGUCCUGCAGUACCUAAAUUUCUCUACAAUAAUUGGAGUUGGUGUUGGAGCUGGAGCCUACAUCCUGGCGAGAUAUGCUCUUAACCACCCGGACACUGUUGAAGGUCUUGUCCUCAUCAACAUUGAUCCCAAUGCCAAGGGUUGGAUGGAUUGGGCAGCCCACAAGCUAACAGGCCUCACCUCUUCCAUUCCGGAGAUGAUCCUUGGACAUCUUUUCAGCCAGGAAGAGCUCUCUGGAAAUUCUGAGUUGAUACAAAAGUACAGAAAUAUCAUUACACAUGCACCCAACCUGGAUAACAUUGAAUUGUACUGGAACAGCUACAACAACCGCCGAGACCUGAACUUUGAGCGUGGAGGUGAUAUCACCCUCAGGUGUCCUGUGAUGCUGGUGGUAGGAGACCAAGCACCUCAUGAAGAUGCAGUGGUGGAAUGUAACUCAAAACUGGACCCCACCCAGACCUCGUUCCUCAAGAUGGCUGACUCCGGAGGUCAGCCCCAGCUGACUCAGCCAGGCAAGCUGACCGAGGCCUUCAAGUACUUCCUGCAAGGCAUGGGCUACAUGGCCUCAUCCUGCAUGACUCGCCUGUCCCGGUCUCGUACAGCCUCUCUGACCAGUGCAGCAUCCGUUGAUGGCAACCGGUCCCGCUCUCGCACCCUGUCCCAGAGCAGCGAGUCUGGAACUCUUUCUUCGGGGCCCCCGGGGCACACCAUGGAGGUCUCCUGUUGAAUGGCCCUUGUUGCCCUAGAGUGGGACCCAGCCCUCACCUCCCCCAGAGCUAACCUGGGAGGUGCUGAAGGGGCAUUGGGCCACCGUAAGCAAGGGAAAAAGGGCAGAUCAUGCGGGGAGAUGACCUUGAUCUUUGAUUGCUACCCUAACCUUGACCUUUAACCCGUGAUUCCCCCCAGCUCCUGGAAGAGAUGUCCUAAUAUCUCUUAGGGACCCAGACCCCUAAAUUCUCCUCCUCCCCCAUUUUGAUGUUAAGGUGGAGAGGGCAUAUGCAUCCUCUGUCCUGAUCUAGGUGUCUAUAGCUGAGGGGUAAGAGGUUGUUGUAGUUGUCCUGGUGCCUCCAUCAGACUCUCCCUACUUGUCCCAUAUUUGCAAGGGGAGGGGAUUUGGGGCUGGGGCUCCAUUCACCAAAGCUGAGGUGGCUUCUCAUUAACCCUUUAGGACUCUGAAGGGUAUGGACCUACGUGAAUGUGUGUCAGGGGGAGACUUGCUGGUGGGUUAGUGGUCCUCAGGAUGUGAUAGAAACAUCCAGUGUAAAAAGGAAGUUGGAAUGGGAGUUGGCGGGCAGUGAACGAGUGUGGGGAAGGAUUGGUGCUGGGGCAACAGGAAGGGGCCUGGGGCCGUUUGGCUGCACUAACUUUGGUAGCUCAGUGUGCAUCUAGAGUGGGACUGGGGAGGGAGCUAAGCUUGGGCUGGGCUGCUUGGGGCUUGGCAUAGGGUGGAAAGGGCUACCCUGGGGCUCUGACCACACUGUAGUAUGUGUGGAGGGUGCCCUCCCGUCUCCCACAACUUCUGCUAUAACAAUAAACUGUAGAGGAAUCUGA